AUUGGCGGAGACGGUUGCGCGUUGGAGGCCCGAGCGGCCCAGCCCGCGGCCCGCUCCGUGUCAGUCAGUCAUGGAGCGGCCGCCCAGAGCGGCGGCGGGGGCGGCGGGGCGCGGGGCGCGGGGGCCCAGCUGAGCCGGCCGUCGGAGUGAGACCCUGCGGCAGAGACGACGGAGGCGGAAGCAACCCGAUCCCGGAGGCGGCGGCGGCGGGGGGAGCCGGAGCCGCCUGGGAUGUUCAGUCAUGAAACGAGUGCGUACCGAGCAGAUUCAGAUGGCAGUGUCCUGCUACCUCAAACGCCGGCAGUACGUGGACUCAGAUGGUCCCCUGAAGCAAGGACUGCGGCUGUCACAGACUGCUGAAGAGAUGGCGGCCAAUCUAACAGUGCAAUCAGAAUCUGGUUGUGCCAACAUAGUGUCUGCAGCCCCUUGCCAGGCAGAACCCCAGCAAUAUGAAGUACAGUUUGGACGACUGCGGAAUUUUCUCACUGAUUCUGAUUCCCAGCAUAGCCACGAAGUGAUGCCUCUCCUCUAUCCUCUCUUUGUCUACCUCCAUCUCAACCUGGUCCAAAACAGUCCGAAGAGCACAGUGGAAAGUUUUUACAGCCGCUUCCAUGGAAUGUUUCUGCAGAAUGCUAGCCAGAAGGAUGUCAUUGAGCAGCUACAGACCACUCAAACCAUCCAGGACAUCCUAUCUAACUUCAAGCUUCGAGCAUUCCUAGAUAACAAGUACGUGGUCCGUCUCCAAGAAGACAGCUACAACUACCUUAUCCGCUACCUCCAAAGUGACAACAAUACUGCCCUGUGCAAAGUCCUCACCUUACAUAUUCAUCUUGACGUGCAGCCUGCCAAGAGAACAGACUAUCAGCUGUAUGCCAGUGGCAGCUCCUCCCGCAGUGAGAACAACGGUUUGGAGCCCCCCGACAUGCCCAGCCCUAUUCUGCAGAACGAGGCUGCCCUAGAGGUCUUACAGGAGAGCAUUAAGCGAGUCAAGGAUGGGCCUCCCUCCCUCACUACCAUCUGCUUCUAUGCCUUCUAUAACACAGAGCAGCUGUUGAACACUGCAGAAAUCUCCCCCGAUAGCAAGCUGCUUGCUGCUGGGUUUGACAACUCCUGUAUAAAACUUUGGAGUUUACGAUCCAAGAAGUUAAAAUCAGAGCCCCACCAAGUAGACGUGUCCCGCAUCCAUUUGGCUUGUGAUAUUCUGGAGGAGGAGGUAUGAAUACCAUUUUUUUCUUCCCUGCACCCGCCUUCCUAAUUUCCUUAGAAUGUCCUUACCAAACACGACAUAUCUUAGAAUGGACUUCCUAGUUUCCCUCAUCAUAUAGCUAAAGCCAGACUAAUGACAUGUUACCUGUAGCCAUUGAAUUCCUGCACAUGCCUAACCUAAGAUGCAAAAACAAUUUUUAGCAGCAUUAACUUCUUAUUAAUGAAUGGUCAGUAUUUAUACUAUGUGAAAUGUGGAUAGCAACACUAAGCCUAAUGAAAGACCUUUAGCUAAUAUUGACUUUAGCUGAGAUUUGCAGUAAAUAUACACUUAUGUGUGUGCACAUUUGCUCAGGUACAAAUAAUCGGUAGUAGGAUAACUGAGUCGAAGGGCCUCCAUUGUCAACUGUAAUGAAUAUUAUUUUCCCCACAGAAGGUUGUGCCAUUUCACAGUCUCAGCAACAGUAGUAAGAAUACUGGCAUCCCUGCACCCUCACCACACUGGAUGGAUGGUAUUGGCUUUCUGAGGCCAGUGCAUAUCCUGUGGCUCCAUGUACCCCGGGGUGUUCCCAGACCCCACUUGGAGAAGUAACACAGGAAGUAGAGUUGCCAGCUCCCCUCCCCCCGUCAGUCAGUGUUCAAUCUUGUUUGGCUUGUAACCGUUUAGGACAGUCAUUGAAAAGGGCAGGCGCAGCUUGGGUUUCAGGUCACCAAAAAUCACUACCUUAGAAAAAAUGUGGGCCAAGGAAGAUAGAAAUUAAACUUCACAGCAUUAACUUUUCUUUAGAGUGGUCCUGAAAAAGCUGUGGGCCAAAGUAUUUUUGUCUUAUCACCACUGAAAUUCAGGUAGCUCUGCCUCACAUUACUUUGGAUGGAAAAUUCUUUACACAAUGUUGAAUAAUUAAGGAGCAAAAAAAUCACUCUAAUUAAAUUACAGUUAAUGAUAAGGAUGUCAAGAAUAUUGGGUGCCCUAAAUUAAACCAUUGUUUUCCUGUUCCUGUUUUCUGAGUCCACUUCCAGUUAGGAUGGCCUUUGAAUUUUUGAUUCUUGCAACCGAGACAGUAUAAUUGAAGGAUUUCCUUGUGAUGAGUGAAGAGUCUAGAUUCCCAUGUAGAAGCUUUAAUUUCUAGAAUUUUAUAGUACUCUCCAAAAUAUUUUUUAUUACAUUUGUAUUUGAAUUUUCAAACAUCUCUUUUCCUUGGAGACAGUUCCCUUUUUGGGAGUUCUUCUGAUAAAACUGAGGAAUACUGCCUGCAUUUGCUUUCGAUUUUCUGUAAAUACAAAAAAAAAUUACACUGACCUUAUUAGCUUUGAUGAUACAGAGUUUGGAGAUUAUUCUGUGCAUUAAAAAUUAAUAUUAAAGAAGAUAGCAUUAUGACAUCUGAUAACAGUAGACCAAAAUAAAACAUUUUAAGACUCUGGCCACUACUGGUAACUAGCUCUGUGGCUUGUCCUAUGUUUAUUUCCGGGUAUCAGAAGUGUAUCUGAAGACUCAGAAGUGAGGAACCGCAUGCGGAAUUCCAGGAACUGAAAGAAAUUAAGUAUGGCUGGAGUUAGGAGAGGGGCCAAGACAGGAAGUGAUGUAGUGACACUGUCUUAUAUGAGCAAUUAUGGCGGCCAAACUAGGGUAGUGGCAGUGGCAAAGGAGACAUGGAUGGACUAGAGAAGAGCUCGGUUAUUCAAUUACUGUAGGGGAUAAGGGAGAGCAAGCAUCAAGGGUGACGUUUGUGUUUCAGGCUUAAACAGUUGGAUGUCCAUCAAGAAGAAAGCAAAAGACGUCAUUGGAAUGGUGGUUUUGUUUAAGCAUUUCUGGCUUUCCAUCAUGGUUCAUACUGAAAGUACUGUAGAUGCUAGCUAACCUCUGCCCUUUUUAAGAAUAAACCUUUUUUUUAAACUUAAGAACUAAAGCUGAGAUUCUCCUAUUCUGUUGUUGAGGGGCUUCCUGCAUGCCCGCCCAUUUUAUCACAGCAAUUUGAGAAGUUUUCUUUUUGGUUUCUGACAACAAGCAUUUGGGGAGAAAGCCAGGCAUAAAUUAGUUACGAUAGUUGGUGUUUAAUGUUUCUCCAGUGAAAAUUUGGACUUUUCUUUUUCCCUUAUAGAAUGCAUAAUUAAAACAGACUAUUAUUUUGAAAUGAAAUAUUGAAUAUUAAAAAAAAUAAAAUAGAGACUCUUAAUACAGGAGCCACAAACUCACAUACCUAGAGAAACCAAACAGGUAAAAGCAAGUGGUGAAGCCACAUGGAUUAAUGAGAUGAUAGAAAGUACAAAAUCACUAUGUAAGUCAGAUUAAAAAGCCAGCUUGCACUCUCUGCUUUCAUCUUUUUGAAGCAAUAACUAUUACAUAAAUCAGUGAAUACAGUAUUUCUACAGUAUUUGAAACGGUGUUCACACCCAGCAAUUCCACUUCUAGACAUAUAUCCAAGAGAAUGGAAAACAUGUGCACACAGGCACUUGUACAUGAAUAUUUAUGGAAGCAUUAUUCACAAUAGCCAAAAAGUGGAAACAGUCCAAAUGGCCAUCAAGAUGAAUGAAUAAAUAAAAUGUAGUGUGUGCAUGCAGUGGAAUAUUAUUUGCCCAUAAAAAGAAAUGAAGCACUGAUGCAGGCUGCAACAUGGAUGAACUUGAAAGCUUUAUGCUACGUGAAAGAAGCCAGUCAUAAAAGGUCACCUACUGUUAUUCCUUUCAUAGGAAAUAUCCAGAUAGGCAAGUCCAUAGAGACAGAGAGGAGAGGAGUGGUUGCCAGGGGCUGGGCAAGGAGAAUGAGAGUGACCGCUAAUGGGUGUGGCAUUUCUUUGUGAGGUAAUGAAAAUGUUCUGUAUUAGAUAGUGGUGAUCAUUGCACAACUCUGUGAAUGUACUAAAAAUCAUUGAAUUGUACACUUUGAAAGAAUUAUAUAGUAUGUAAUUAUAUCUCAGUUUAAAAAAAAAAACAGGAUAACAGUAACCAAAAUCUUCUAUGUAAGCUUAAAAUUUUCUCUGUUAAUUAUGCCAAAUAAAACUGAAUUCACAGCA